AGGCCAGAGGAUGUGGAGGGCGUGACUGCACCUGGCCCCAGGAGCUGGUUAGAACCCAGCUGAGGCUCUGCCAGGAGAGGAGAGCAUCUCUAUCUCAGCACUGUGCAGGGUCUGCCGAGAGUUCCAGAGUUUGAAGGGGCCUGAAGGACACUGCAGUUCAACACCCACCACAGGGCUAUGGCUUCCCUAACAGGGAGUAGACUCUGCUCAGUCACCUCCAGUGAGGGCCCCUCACUACCUCCAGAAGCAGCCUGUGUCUCUGGCAGCCCUAGUCCUCAGAAUGCUUCCUUCAGAGGAAUGCUGCUGUGCCCCUGCAGCAUGAUACCCCAUCUUCUCUUCCUUGUGACAGCCCUGUCAUGCUGGGGACCUAAACUUCUACCUCCGAAAUCUCCUCUGUACCUGCUGGGGACAUUCCUUCGUGUGAGGACCCCAUCAGCCUCACUGGCCUGGGACUCCUCGUGGACCCAGAGCCAUGGCCCACAGCCUGCCAAGUAGAAAUUCCUGCUCCAAAGAGCCUGUUCCUUAUCAGCUCAUCCACCCCUGGUGGAGCCUUUCAACUCCUGCCCCAGUGCGUUCAGCUGGGAGGAUGGGAGGUGUGUCUGGUUCCUCUGCCUUCCUCUCCCCGCUGCUUCCAUCCUGCCCUCCCCAGGAAUCUCCUGGUUUCUGUGGCUCCGACCCUCCUCCUCAGAAAGCUCAAGCUCAUUCCAGGCUCUUCUGUCAUGUCAGGCAUGUUUGUUGCUGAAACUGGGCAUGGGUUAGACUUGUGUACACAAGCAGUUUGUGGCAGACCUGCUAUGUGCUUCAGGGCAUUGGCCCAGCUGCUGGGGGGCAAAUGGAAUCAGCUACAUUAUCCUUAGUCUUGCUCUCAAGAAAAUCCUGCCUUUUGGGGCAGAGGAGGUGGGCAGAUGGUUGGACAACUGGCUGCCCACCAAGGCAGAACGCCAUUGGGCCUCAACAGAGCAGUGAGCAGAGUGCCAGCAGGUUUGACCUCUCCCUGGAGAGGCUUGUCAGCUGAGCACCGUGAGAGAGCAGGAUUUGGGUAGGCAGAGAACCAGAGAAGGGAAUUCCAGGCUGAGGGAAUGGCUGGAGCAAACGCUUCGAGGUGGGAGGAUGCCUUUUCUGUUGGGGGCCGGUGAGAGGCCUGUUGUGGUUGGACUACAGGAUGCCACAUCAGAGCUAUGGUGGGGGUAGAGAAAGGACAAGUGGGGUGGAGGGUCCCCUCUCAGCCACACAGCAGCCUGGAGGAAGGGGAGAGGAGAGAAGAACUGAUGGGCUGGGAUCCCCAGCUCUCCCUGUCCCCCAGGCGCCUGGGGACUGGCACCCUGUCUAAAACUGUAACAUCCUCUUCAUUGACAGUGUUUUCAUUUCUUGCUUAGCAGUGAUCAGCACUGACAUGCUGUCCAUUUACUCAUCACCCCCACCAUUUACACACAGGUGCACUUGAGUGCCAGCUCUGCCAGGGAAGGAUUUGUGUCCCUUUCUUCCCUGCUGUAUUCCCCGUGCCUCAAACAGUGCCUGGCACAGAGCAGGUGGACGACCCACCGGAGCCCGUGUACGCGAACAUAGAGAGGCAGCCCCGGGCCACUUCACCGGGCGCCGCUGCAGCCCCCCUUCCCAGCCCGGUGUGGGAGACGCACACGGACGCGGGCACCGGGCGCCCCUACUACUACAACCCAGACACGGGAGUUACCACCUGGGAGUCGCCCUUUGAGGCUGCCGAGGGUGCCGCCAGCCCAGCCACCUCCCCUGCCUCGGUGGACAGCCACGUGAGCCUUGAGACCGAGUGGGGCCAGUACUGGGAUGAGGAGAGCCGCAGGGUGUUCUUCUACAACCCGCUGACGGGCGAGACGGCCUGGGAGGACGAGGCCGAGAACGAGCCCGAGGAGGAGUUGGAGAUGCAGCCGGGCCUGAGCCCUGGCAGCCCAGGGGACCCGCGGCCCCCCACUCCCGAGACGGACUACCCCGAGUCGCUGACCAGUUACCCCGAGGAGGACUAUUCUCCCGUGGGCUCUUUCGGUGAGCCCGGCCCUACCUCUCCCUUGACCACACCCCCCGGCUGGUCUUGUCAUGUCAGCCAGGACAAGCAGAUGCUCUACACCAACCACUUCACUCAGGAGCAGUGGGUGAGGCUGGAGGACCCCCACGGGAAGCCAUACUUCUACAAUCCAGAGGACUCCUCUGUUCGAUGGGAGCUGCCCCAGGUCCCUGUCCCUGCCCCUCGAAGCAUCCAUAAAUCCAGCCAGGAUGGUGACACCCCAGCCCAGGCCAGCCCUCCAGAGGAGAAGGUCCCAGCAGAGCUGGAUGAGGUUGGGAGCUGGGAGGAAGUCUCUCCUGCCACAGCUGCUGUGAGGACCAAGACCUUGGACAAGGCAGGGGUGCUCCAUCGCACCAAGACGGCAGACAAGGGAAAGCGGCUCCGGAAGAAGCACUGGAGUGCCUCCUGGACUGUGCUGGAGGGUGGCGUCCUGACAUUCUUCAAGGACUCAAAGACCUCGGCUGCAGGCGGCCUGAGGCAGCCUUCCAAGUUUUCCACCCCUGAGUACACAGUGGAGCUGAGGGGGGCCACUCUCUCCUGGGCCCCCAAAGACAAAUCCAGUAGGAAGAAUGUGCUGGAGCUACGGAGCCGAGAUGGCUCUGAGUACCUGAUCCAGCACGACUCGGAGGCCAUCAUCAGCACCUGGCAUAAGGCCAUUGCUCAGGGCAUCCAGGAGCUGUCCGCAGAGCUGCCCCCAGAGGAGAGCGAGAGCAGCAGAGUGGACUUCGGGUCGAGCGAGCGCUUGGGAAGCUGGCAGGAGAAAGAGGAGGACGCGCGACCGAAUGCAGCCGCGCCCGCCCUGGGCCCCGUGGGCCUGGAGAGCGACUUGAGCAAGGUCCGGCACAAGCUCCGCAAGUUCCUCCAGAGGCGGCCCACACUGCAGUCGCUGCGGGAGAAGGGCUACAUCAAAGACCAGGUGUUCGGCUGCGCGCUGGCCGCGCUGUGUGAGCGCGAGAGGAGCCGGGUGCCACGCUUCGUGCAGCAGUGCAUCCGCGCCGUCGAGGCCCGCGGGCUGGACAUCGACGGGCUGUACCGCAUCAGUGGAAACCUGGCCACCAUCCAGAAGCUACGCUAUAAGGUGGACCACGAUGAGCGCCUUGACCUGGAUGACGGGCGCUGGGAGGACGUCCACGUUAUCACCGGAGCCCUGAAGCUCUUCUUUCGGGAGCUGCCCGAGCCCCUCUUCCCCUUCUCGCACUUCCGCCAGUUCAUUGCGGCCAUCAAGUUGCAGGACCAGGCCCGGCGCAGCCGCUGUGUGCGUGACUUGGUGCGCUCGCUGCCCGCUCCCAACCACGACACUCUGCGGAUGCUCUUCCAGCACCUCUGCCGGGUGAUCGAGCACGGCGAGCAGAACCGCAUGUCGGUGCAGAGCGUGGCCAUUGUGUUCGGGCCCACGCUGCUGCGGCCCGAGGUGGAAGAGACCAGCAUGCCCAUGACCAUGGUGUUCCAGAACCAGGUGGUGGAGCUCAUCCUGCAGCAGUGCGCGGACAUCUUCCCGCCGCACUGACUGCUGGCCUGUGACUGGGGCGGCGGCCGCGGUCCUGCCACACAAGCUGGGCGGCGGAGGCCACGCAGCCGGGCCUUCUUCUCUCUGGGACCCUCCGCCAGCGCAUAGCCGCAGGCCGGUGUGACUUCUGCACCCUCGGUUCUGAGGGUACGGUGACCCCUAGUGGGCAGUUUGCAAAAUGUGAUUCCUUCUUCCCAACUCCCCAUCCCCCCUUCCCUUCCCGUCACGUCCUGUUUGGGGGUUAAUUCGGUUUUUUCUCUGUUGCAUCGCGCCUACUGUGCGUGUGCGAUAGCGUGUGUGGGGGUGAGAGUUUGUUUUCUGGAAUGGUAGGUGCUGGGAGGAGGAGUUUGAUGGAGGGCUUCCUGGCUGCUUCUGGCCCUCACCUCGUGGAGGCCUUCACAGAGACCCUGUGGGCCCUGGCCCUGUGCUGGCACUGUGCCAGUCAUGAGGCAGCUCUGAUCACUUCCCCACUGUGGAAACAGGACUGACCCAGCCUUCAGUGUGGGCUGCUGAAGCUAUCCUCCUCAGGCCUCAGGGAUGACCUCCUGCCUGAGCCUCUCACAGGCUGGCUGUGGGCCAGUUUCAUCUGCUUUCCUGUUGGGGGUCCCGGGCCUCUGCUGUCCUUGACCCACUGGUGUUCUGUGCAAGGCUUCUUCCCAUUCACCAAGUGCACACCUUGCAUCUGCCGCUCGGCAUGCACCAGUUCCACACACCAUCCCAUUUUACAGACAAGGACGCUGAGGCCUGCAGCAGCAGUGUGACUUGCUCAAGGUCCAGUGAGUGACCUCAUUCCCCAGAAAAGGCUCCUCCCACACCAGAGUACAGCCUGGGUAGGGGGAAAAUCAGUUCUUUCAGCUACCACCCAUCCAACCUUUGGGCCUAUGUGAAAAGAAAGGAACUAAGCUGGGUGUGUUCUGUCUGGACCUGGGGAGGCCCCUGAAGGCAAAGAGGGAAACUGUCCCAGCUGUUCUGUCCUAGGGGAGGGGGACAUAGCCCUAGCAGGAGCUCCCAGCCCCUCUUGGCACUCUGACACACAAGUACACCCAUCUGGGGCCCGCUUUGCCACGAAGAGCUGGGCAGGCCUGCAGGGUGUGGGGAAGGAGGACACAACCUCAAGAAAGGAAGCGUGAACCCCAGGGAACAGCGGGUCCCUUCCCUCCUCAGACACAAGCCACCUCAGCUUGUGGCUCUUGGCCCCCAGCCCCACCAACCCACCUGUUCAUUUAUUCAACAGACAAUGACAGCUGAUAUUUAUUGGACAUUUGCACCAUGCCAAGCAUUCGGCUUGGAUUAUCCCAUUUGUUUCUCACAGCCGGUAUUUAUUGUCUGCUCCUCUGUGCCAGGUGCUGUGCUCUGGGCAGGGGCACUGCAUGGGCUGCCUGCCCUGGUGGAGCUUGUGGUCUGAUGGGUGAGGCUGACCCAAGCCCACCCCAUUGCCAACAGGGCCAGGGCAAGAGUACACACAGGGGCCUCAUACCAUAUGUCUAAAUAUUUAAAAGUUAUCAAUCAAGCUAACAACUGUUAAAUAAAAUAUGUUCUAUUCUCCUA